AGUCUCAGCCGACACUGCGCGCGCCUCCAGGCACCGGCGUUAGCGGGUCGCCGACCCGCAAUCCCCGCCGCGGCUGCUUGCCUACCGGAGUGUGCGCCGGCACCUGCCGCCGGAGACAUGUUGCAAAAACCGAGGAACCGGGGCCGCUCUGGCGGCCAGGCCGAGAGGGACAGAGACUGGAGCCAUAGCGGAAACCCCGGGGCUUCGCGGGCCGGGGAAGACGCCCGGGUUCUCAGAGACGGCUUUGCCGAGGAGGCCCCGAGCACGUCCCGCGGGCCGGGCGGCUCGCAGGGGUCGCAGGGCCCCUCGCCUCAGGGCGCCCGCCGGGCCCAGGCCGCCCCCGCCGUGGGGCCCAGGAGCCAGAAGCAGCUGGAGCUGAAAGUGUCCGAGCUGGUGCAGUUCUUGCUGAUUAAAGACCAGAAGAAGAUUCCGAUCAAGCGGGCCGACAUACUGAAGCACGUCAUCGGGGACUACAAGGACAUCUUCCCCGACCUCUUCAAACGGGCCGCCGAGCGCCUCCAGUACGUCUUCGGGUAUAAGCUGGUGGAACUUGAACCCAAGAGCAACACUUACAUCCUCAUCAACACCCUGGAGCCUGUGGAGGAGGAUGCCGAGAUGAGGGGUGACCAAGGCACGCCCACUACGGGCCUCCUGAUGAUCGUCUUAGGGCUCAUCUUUAUGAAGGGCAACACCAUCAAGGAAACUGAAGCCUGGGACUUUCUGCGGCGCUUAGGGGUCUACCCCACCAAGAAGCAUUUAAUUUUCGGAGAUCCAAAGAAACUCAUUACUGAGGACUUUGUGCGACAGCGUUACCUGGAAUACCGGCGGAUACCCCACACCGACCCCGUCGACUACGAAUUCCAGUGGGGCCCGCGAACCAACCUGGAAACCAGCAAGAUGAAAGUUCUUAAGUUUGUGGCCAAGGUCCAUAAUCAAGACCCCAAGGACUGGCCAGCGCAGUACUGUGAGGCUUUGGCAGAUGAGGAGAACAGGGCCAGACCUCAGCCUAGUGGCCCAGCUCCAUCCUCUUGAAAGGUGGAUUCAGAGGGACCCCCGGGACAAGGGUCUGAGACCCAAAGGCACAGUUUAGAGGAUUGGGGGAAGGGAGAACGAACCCAGGGAGCAUAUUGCUGUAAACGCUUCAAUGUGUGUAGCUUUAGGAUGUGUUUGCAAAGUUUUGUUUUUUUAAUGUUGUGUUAUUUUGCUCCAGAUUUUCAUCUAUAAACAAAGGAGCAUUUGUUUUGAUUUUACUCUUUUUGGUAUAAAAAAUUUUGCUAGCUUAGUAAAACGAAUUGGAAAACUUGACUAUGAUCUGGAACAGAUAAUGCAAGAAGGAACACAUAAGUAAGUUGCUUUGGUGCCAAGAAAAUAAAAAAGCUAUUAUCAGGUCUCCUAACUACCCCAGUUUGUAAGGAAAAAUAAAAGUUUUUAUAAAAUUAAAAAAAAUAAUUGCCUAUAUCCUUAUUAUGUUAACCUAUUUUAUUUUUCUAUAUUUCGUACAUAUAUAAGUAUUAUUCAUGGUUCCAAGCAAUGAGUGUAAUGUAUUUUCUCCCAAUAGUAAUUGUUUAUAUUCAUAAUUAUUCAGCUCUGCUGCUAAACACGUAGUUCCACUUCGUUUUUUUCUUCUUGCUACUGUAGUUAUUACAAUAAAUACUGUAUUUUUGAAGCACUUAAGCAUUGUGUGUUUUUUAAAUCGUGGGUCAUGAGAGAAUUUCAUGACUGGAAAUCAACAUCUUAAAGUUUUUGCUACAUAUUAAGGUCAAUGCUGUUUUGUAGAAGUUGUUUCACUUUUGUGUGAAACAAAAUCAGGAUCAUGAGGUGAAAUAUAUUUCUCACUGUGGAUCUCAAAAAGGCUUAUAAAACAAUAGCGUAACCAUUAACCAUGCCUGUUUGGGAAUCGGACUGUCUGGGUUGAGAUCCUGGCCCCACCAUAACUAGUAUAUGAAUUUACAUAGGUUCCUUAGUUUGUAUGCAGAUGUUUCUUGACCUGUAAAAUGGUUUUAGUCCGUGAUGUGGAGAAUUUUAUUUGUUAUUCUUUAAUGUUUUUAUUUUUUAUUCUCCUUGGUCUGGAGCUGCCACUUUUUAAAUAUAACUUUUCUUUAUCUUUUUUUCCAAAUCAUUCCUAGGAGAGCAAUUCCUGGUUCAAAAGAUAGUCCUCUAGUCUCACUCUAUUGUAUGGGGAAAUAUAACGUGUAUGGUGAGUGUGCCCCACAUAGAACAUAAGAGCAGGACAUAAGAUCUACCUCCUAGGGAGUUAGGUAUAGGGAAAAGGGUAUGGGUCUUGGGGCUGUCUGGCAAACUGAAUUUGAAUUACGGCUCAUGCUAACUUGUCAGCAUGGUGGUUGUGGGGGUAGGUUUUAAGCUCUCUGAAUCUCAAUUUAUCUGUAAAAUGAGAAAAAUAAUAGCUAUAUAAUAGUUUUAUGCACUAAAUGAACUAGAAGAGUUCAUAGUCCCAUUGUGUUCCUCCAUUACGUGUAGCAGAUGCUGUUUUUAAUGCAGAGAUUCAACACGUUUUAUUCAGUGGGCAAAUAAGUUAAUUGUUUUAGGGGGAGGUGCUGCAAAUUAACCUUGAAAUAAGGCAAAUAUUUUUAACUCGGGGAAAAAAGUGAACUUCAUCAACACUGGACGGAAUGUCAUUUAAAAGAGUCUAUAGUGAGUAUGGAGGAAUGUGAUAGGUUACUGGGUUUUAUUUCAUUCUGUUGAAUUGGGAUUUGCAUUUGUUUCAUCAGUGGAAUAUGUUUGGCCCUUACAGGCAUUUCUUCUUGAUCUGCAUUUUAUUUCAGUGUAUAAACUCCUUCCUGCCUCCUGGUCCCCUUACCUCCCUGACUCAGCUUUCUCCUCCUCAUGCCCUCUGAUACUCGCAUUCUCACCUGUAUAAUAAAAAUUAUUACCCAGCAGUCACCACCAGUUAUAUCUGAGGCAAAAUUCCCCCCGCUUUUCUCAGAGGUGUUAGCAAUUUACCAUCGAUAAUCUUGUUUCAAAUUUUAAAAUAUGAAACAUCAGAGGCCACAUCAAGGCCUUAUAUCUUUUCCUUCUCACCCUCCCCAGAGGUAACAAAAGUCUGUGGCUAUCGGGCUGUUGUAUGACUUUAUAAUUUUACUAUACAUGUAUAUAUACAUAACCAAUAUAGAGUUUUAUUUUGUGGGCUUUCAUGAUUUAUAUAAGCGGUGUUACGUGUGUCCUUAUGCAACUUGCUGUACUCACUCACCAUUAUGUAUUUGAGAUUCAGCCAUGUGGAUAUAUGUAGACCUGAUUCACUCAUUUUAAUUGUUCUUUUAUGGGGGAAAAAUAACUAUCCAUUCCUUAAUGUCUGGACAUUUAAGGUCUUUCCAGUUCUUUGAGAUUUGCAGGCAUUGUACAGUACUUCUUUAGGCACAUGUGUGAGUUUCUCCAGCCAGAAACAAAUGGAGCAAUCAAGGACUAUUGCCAAGCUGCUCUUGAGCUUGUGUCAAGUUACACUCCCAUCAACAUUUUAUACAGUUUUGUUUUGUUUUUGUUUACCAAUCCCUCCACCUUCACCCCCUGUGAACACUUGGCCUUUUCAGUAUCUUUUCAGCCAUUCUGGUACAGUGUGAAAUGAUAAUUUAUUACGGUAUUAACUUAUACCUGUUGCUUACUAGUAAUGUUAAGUAUCUGCCUAUCUUUUGCUCUCACUCCUUUUUGAGUGUCAGAUUUCAUGUCUUAGACCUAUUUCUAUUGAUUUGUAAGACAUCUUUAUAUGUUCUACAUGUUAAUCCAUGGUCUGCUCUAUCUAUCUAGUGCAAAUACCUUCUCCCACAUUUUCACUUCUUUUGGUCAUACAGAUCAUUUGACCUAAAUGUGUUACGAUCAUUAGUGUUUAUAAGAGCUACAUUUGUGUAUAGUGCUUUAAAAAAUUCCCCUAAUCCUAAAAUUGUAAAUAUGUUUUCUGCCUUUUUUCCCUAAGUGUUCAAAGUUUUGAUCUUCACAUUUUAUGCUUUUAAUCUGCUUUUGUGUAUGAUGUGAGGUAUGGAAAUAGUUUUUGUAUUUUUCCUAUAUGGAUAGCCUAGCACCAGUUUUUCAUCAUUUAUACUUUCCACACUGAUUUAUGACACUCAGUAUUUUGUAGCAAUGUCCCAUGUAUAGAUAAAUUUAUGGCUAGGACUGAAUUGGUUUAUUUGCUAUCCAUUUGCAAAUACCAUACUGUAAUUCUUUUUUUCUUUUUGAGACGGAGUCUUGCUCUUGUCGCCCAGGCUGGAGUGCAUUGGCACAAUCUUGGCUCAGUGCAAUCUCUGCCUCCUGGAUUCAAGCGAUUCUCCUGCCUCAGCCUCCUGAGUAGCUGGGAUUACAGGUGCCCGCCACCACGUCCGGCUAAUUUUUGUACUUUUAGUAGAGACGGGGUUUUGCCAUGUUGGCCAGGGUGGUCUCAAACUCCUGACUUUAGGUAAUCUGCCCGCCUCGGCCUCCUAAAGUGCUAGGAUUACAGGCAUGAGCCACCUCGCCCAGCCUAUAAUUCUUUAGCAUCAUAUGCCUGUCUUCUUUUUCAAUUCUUAAAGCCUUUUAUUUUAGUCUUUUUUGCAUUGGCUGAAAAUGCAAUAUAUUAUUGAAAAGAAGCAGUUACAGCAGGCUCUAAGGAUGUUUCUGAUUCCUUAUUCUUGAUUUUAAAGGAAAUAAUUUUAAGUUUUGCCAUAGAGUGUGAUGUUUGCUGUUAAGAGUUUUUUUCCCCUAUAAAUACCUUUUAUUGGGCUAUUUAGUUACCCCUUCAGUCCUAGCUUGCUUAGAGAUGUUCAGAAAAAAAACUAUGAAUGACUUUGGAUGUAUAUAUGCUCUUUAUUUACCUGCUAAUAUGAUUAAAAUGUCUUAUUUACUCUGUAAA